AGAGCACUCAUCAGCAUGCUUCCUCCUCUCUAACUGUGUCCUUUAGAUCCAGGAGGGAUAUUUGCUACCACCACCAGCUAAUGCUGAUUUGCUACCAGCACAAGGCCCAGGUCCUUGUCUGGUCUGUACCCCAUUACAAGGUUCUCCAGGAACAGACAUCACCACCUCUGCCUAGAUCCUGAAAUUUCACAAAUGUAGGUUCUUUCUUACCCGUUCUUUUUAUUCCUCUAUUUACAAGCACAAUGACACCCACCCCUCGUCUUCUUCCUGAAAUACCUGGCUCUGAUCCCAGGCAUCCAUUCCAGAAAUCAACACAGCUAUGCAAUUGCAUCUUUUAUUAAAUACUCCCAACUCCAUUUCAAAUCCAGAGAAUCCAGAGCAGGAGCAAGAGACCAACCUAUCAUCUGGAAACUCAAGGUGUAAACAUUAGUGCCAAAGAUUAGUCAUGAAGGCCAACUACAGCGCAGAGGAGCGCUUUCUCCUGCUGGGUUUCUCCGACUGGCCUUCCCUGCAGCCGGUCCUCUUCGCCCUUGUCCUCCUGUGCUACCUCCUGACCUUGACGGGCAACUCGGCGCUGGUGCUGCUGGCGGUGCGCGACCCGCGCCUGCACACGCCCAUGUACUACUUCCUCUGCCACCUGGCCUUGGUAGACGCGGGCUUCACUACUAGCGUGGUGCCGCCGCUGCUGGCC